CUUUUCAGUUCGUCCAUCUUCUAGAAACGAGUCCCCGAGACCCCGGGCUGCCUUCUUGGGGCUGCUCCGCCUCCUGACCAGCCCUCGUCAGCCACUCGAAGUCCCUGAGGAGACGUGGAGAGGAGGAGGGACACGGCAUGGGGGGAGUCCGGGAAGGGAGACGAGCGUCUGAAGACGUCCUCCCGAGGGCAGAAGGGGCCGGGGGAGCUGGCGCAGGGCUCUCUACCUAGCGCUGCAGGCUCCUGGGCGAUUGUAGCGGGACCGUCACACACAACUGGCACCCAGGCCAGGGGUCCAGAGCUAAAUUCUGCCUGCAGGAGCGGUUAUUGUGGCAUCCGUUUCUAAAAAGUUUAAAGGCAACAUUUUAUUUUAUUUUAAUUUUUUUGAGACAAGAUCUGCCUCUGUCGCCCAGGCUGGAGUGCAGUGGCGAGAUCUCAGCUCACUGCAACCUGUGCCUCCCGGCUUCAAGCGAUUCUCAGCCUCAGCCUCCCGAGUAGCUGGGAUUGCAGGCGCCCGCCACCACGCCCGGCUAAUUUUUUUUUUUCUUUUUGUUUUGUUUGAGACUCAGUCUCGCUCUGUUGCCCAGGCUGAAGUGCAGUGGGGCGCUCUCGGCUCACUGCAACCUCUGCCUCCCAGGUUCAAGCGAUUCUCCUGCCUCAGCCUCCCGAGUAGCUGGGAUUACAGGAGCGUGCCACCACUCCGGGCUAAUUUUUGUGUUUUAAGUAGAGAUGGGGUUUCACCAUGUUGGUCAGGCAGAUUUCGAAUUCCUGACCUCAAGUGAUCCACCCGCCUCGGCCUUUAUUUACUUAUUUUUUUUUAAUAGACACGGGGUCAUGUUGCCAGCCAUGUUGCCCAGGCUGGUCGUGAACUCCUGGGCUCAAGUGAUCCUCCCGCCUUGCCCUUGGCCUUCCAAGUGCUAGGAUUACAGGCGUGAGCCACCAACACCCUGCCUGAGGCAACAUUUUAAACUUGGUGUAUGUUGAAAAUUUCAAAACCCCUCAGCUGUCCUGCAUCCUCAUUUAGGUUCCUGCUUGGCUCGAGUUUGAGUUUACAGCCCCUGCAAGUAAAUCCAAGAGCCUGUUACAGAUUGGCGGUCGUGCCUUAUGAAAUCUGACUUCUACUUCCAGAAAUCAGAGCCUCAUUCCCUUAGUAGUGAAGCAUUGAUGAGGAGAGCAGUGUCUUUGGUAACAGAUAGCACCUCUACCUUUCUCUCUCAGACCACAUAUGCGUUGAUUGAAGCUAUUACUGAAUAUACUAAGGCUGUUUAUACCUUAACUUCUCUUUACCGACAAUAUACAAGUUUACUUGGGAAAAUGAAUUCAGAGGAGGAAGAUGAAGUGUGGCAGGUGAUCAUAGGAGCCAGAGCUGAGAUGACUUCAAAACACCAAGAGUACUUGAAGCUGGAAACCACUUGGAUGACUGCAGUUGGUCUUUCAGAGAUGGCAGCAGAAGCUGCAUAUCAAACUGGCGCAGAUCAGGCCUCUAUAACCGCCAGGAAUCACAUUCAGCUGGUGAAACUGCAGGUGGAAGAGGUGCACCAGCUCUCCCGGAAAGCAGAAACCAAGCUGGCAGAAGCACAGAUAGAAGAGCUCCGUCAGAAAACACAGGAGGAAGGGGAGGAGCGGGCUGAGUCGGAGCAGGAGGCCUACCUGCGUGAGGAUUGAGGGCCUGAGCACACUGCCCUGUCUCCCCACUCAGUGGGGAAAGCAGGGGCAGAUGCCACCCUGCCCAGGGUUGGCAUGACUGUCUGUGCACCGAGAAGAGGCGGCAGAUCCUGCCCUGGCCAAUCAGGCGAGACGCCUUUGUGAGCUGUGAGUGCCUCCUGUGGUCUCAGGCUUGCGCUGGACCUGGUUCUUAGCCCUUGGGCACUGCACCCUGUUUAACAUUUCACCCCACUCUGUACAGCUGCUCUUACCCAUUUUUUUUACCUCACACCCAAAGCAUUUUGCCUACCUGGGUCAGAGAGAGGAGUCCUUUUUGUCAUGCCCUUAAGUUCAGCAACUGUUUAACCUGUUUUCAGUCUUAUUUACGUCGUCAAAAAUGAUUUAGUACUUGUUCCCUCUGUUGGGAUGCCAGUUGUGGCAGGGGGAGGGGAACCUGUCCAGUUUGUACGAUUUCUUUGUAUGUAUUUCUGAUGUGUUCUCUGAUCUGCCCCCACUGUCCUGUGAGGACAGCUGAGGCCAAGGAGUGAAAAACCUAUUACUACUAAGAGAAGGGGUGCAGAGUGUUUACCUGGUGCUCUCAACAGGACUUAACAUCAACAGGACUUAACACAGGCCUCUUGUUCCUUCCUUUCUUUCCGUUUCUCUAUUGUAUCCAAAGGAGAAGAGUGUAAGAUUUUGUUUGCAUCUGAAAGAGAAAAUGCGUCUCUCCUGGG